GCAGCAGGCCAAGGGGGAGGUGCGAGCGUGGACCUGGGACGGGUCUGGGCGGCUCUCGGUGGUUGGCACGGGUUCGCACACCCAUUCAAGCGGCAGGACGCACUUGUCUUAGCAGUUCUCGCUGACCGCGCUAGCUGCGGCUUCUACGCUCCGGCACUCUGAGUUCAUCAGCAAACGCCCUGGCGUCUGUCCUCACCAUGCCUAGCCUUUGGGACCGCUUCUCGUCGUCGUCCACCUCCUCUUCGCCCUCGUCCUUGCCCCGAACUCCCACCCCAGAUCGGCCGCCGCGCUCAGCCUGGGGGUCGGCGACCCGGGAGGAGGGGUUUGACCGCUCCACGAGCCUGGAGAGCUCGGACUGCGAGUCCCUGGACAGCAGCAACAGUGGCUUCGGGCCGGAGGAAGACACGGCUUACCUGGAUGGGGUGUCGUUGCCCGACUUCGAGCUGCUCAGUGACCCUGAGGAUGAACACUUGUGUGCCAACCUGAUGCAGCUGCUGCAGGAGAGCCUGGCCCAGGCGCGGCUGGGCUCUCGACGCCCUGCGCGCCUGCUGAUGCCUAGCCAGUUGGUAAGCCAGGUGGGCAAAGAACUACUGCGCCUGGCCUACAGCGAGCCGUGCGGCCUGCGGGGGGCGCUGCUGGACGUCUGCGUGGAGCAGGGCAAGAGCUGCCACAGCGUGGGCCAGCUGGCACUCGACCCCAGCCUGGUGCCCACCUUCCAGCUGACCCUCGUGCUGCGCCUGGACUCACGACUCUGGCCCAAGAUCCAGGGGCUGUUUAGCUCCGCCAACUCUCCCUUCCUCCCUGGCUUCAGCCAGUCCCUGACGCUGAGCACUGGCUUCCGAGUCAUCAAGAAGAAGCUGUACAGCUCGGAACAGCUGCUCAUUGAGGAGUGUUGAACUUCAACCUGAGGGGGCCGACAGUGCCCUCCAAGACAGAGACGACUGAACUUUUGGGGUGGAGACUAGAGGCAGGAGCUGAGGGACUGAUUCCUGUGGUUGGAAAACUGAGGCAGCCACCUAAGGUGGAGGUGGGGGAAUAGUGUUUCCCAGGAAGCUCAUUGAGUUGUGUGCGGGUGGCUGUGCAUUGGGGACACAUACCCCUCAGUACUGUAGCAUGAAACAAAGGCUUAGGGGCCAACAAGGCUUCCAGCUGGAUGUGUGUGUAGCAUGUACCUUAUUAUUUUUGUUACUGACAGUUAACAGUGGUGUGACAUCCAGAGAGCAGCUGGGCUGCUCCCGCCCCAGCCCGGCCCAGGGUGAAGGAAGAGGCACGUGCUCCUCAGAGCAGCCGGAGGGAGGGGGGAGGUCGGAGGUCGUGGAGGUGGUUUGUGUAUCUUACUGGUCUGAAGGGACCAAGUGUGUUUGUUGUUUGUUUUGUAUCUUGUUUUUCUGAUCGGAGCAUCACUACUGACCUGUUGUAGGCAGCUAUCUUACAGACGCAUGAAUGUAAGAGUAGGAAGGGGUGGGUGUCAGGGAUCACUUGGGAUCUUUGACACUUGAAAAAUUACACCUGGCAGCUGCGUUUAAGCCUUCCCCCAUCGUGUACUGCAGAGUUGAGCUGGCAGGGGAGGGGCUGAGAGGGUGGGGGCUGGAACCCCUCCCCGGGAGGAGUGCCAUCUGGGUCUUCCAUCUAGAACUGUUUACAUGAAGAUAAGAUACUCACUGUUCAUGAAUACACUUGAUGUUCAAGUAUUAAGACCUAUGCAAUAUUUUUUACUUUUCUAAUAAACAUGUUUGUUAAAACA